CUCUUCGUGGACUGCAUCCCCCUCUUCCACGGCACCCUGGCCCUCGCCCCCAUGCUGGAGGUGGCUCUCACCCUGGUAAGCGCGGAAAGGGCCCCUUCCCCUUGCAGGCAGCCUGGCCUCCCCUCAGUCAGCAGAGAGGAAGCUGGCCCAGCGGUCGCCCUCCAGCAGGCUCCUAGGACCCGCUCCCUAGGGUUGCCGUGGCCAGGAAUGGGGUGAUCCACGAUGGCGCUUGGGUCUUGGCGCUGAAUAAAUAGCGUCCCGUAGUAGCAGCGACUUUAACCGUCGUGGAUGCUUUUAGAGGCACUUUAAGGCGACGAGUUAUACGUUAGUUUCCUGAAAUCAGUAGCCUUUGUAGAAACAAGUCAUCGUUCACUUGGUGGGGAUUCGACAGAGUUUCCCUUGAGGAUUUCGAGUUGCAGGAAGUGUUCACGUUGUUGGGACAUUAAUCGCUAGGAUUUGGUUCUUCGCACCUUCGCAGAGCCGAUUCCUUAUCUGGCAAAGUGUAAAUGCUUCUUUGGCUGUCGGUACUCGGGCACCCCGGAGCUCAGACACUUGUAGAAAGGUAGUUGCAUGGUCAGAUCUGUGUGAUGCAUCUUAGGCCUGGCUCCCCUUGAUUGAAUGUGCCUGAGCUUUGUGUAAAGAGAAUUUGUUCCCGUUAAUGGUUAACAACUUAUCUAGAAUGUUUCCAUGGCUUUUAAAAGCUAAAGAAUUUCUGUGGGGCCGGGCGCGGUGGCUGACCCCUGUAAUCCUAGCACUUUGGGAGGCCGAGGCAGGCGGAUCACCUGAGGUCAGAAGUUUGAGACCAGCCUGACCAACAUGGUGAAACCCCUUCUCUACUAAAAAUACAAAACUUAGCCGGGCGUGGUGGCGGGCGCCUGUCAUCCCAGCCACUCGGGAGGCUGAGGCAAGAGAAUCGCUUGAACCCAGGAGGCAGAGGUUGCAGUGAGCCGAGAUCACGCCACUGCACUCCAGCCUGGGUGACAGAGCAAGACUCCGUCUCAAAAAAAAAAAAAAAAAAAAAAAAACGAAUUUCUGUGACAUUAAACAGCAGGAGCAGACGAUCUGUCCAACACGCUUUUAUGUUUUUGUUUGCAAUGACAGCUUUAUUGAAGUACAGUGGGAAAAAAGAUGUAGCAUGCAGGUAGACUAGUUGGUAAGUGAAUUUUAGGCAGUAGCUUUUCAGUUCCGGUGAUCAAUGAAGGGAAAAAGACCAUCUAUAAAUUCCAUCGAGUUGUUAAAACCUGAAGGAAAAGUAAACUGUAGCUUCAGACCUGCAUACCUGAGCUGAGGUGCUGUUUGUUUUUCAUUUAAGAAUAAACUGUGAUGCUAAAAAAUAGUAGCUAAUUGAUGUAAGAAGUAGCUAAGCUUGAGAAGGUGUAAGUAGAAUUUCUUUAUCUGUGUCCCUCCUCCACCAAGUAAAACGAAGCCAUUUCAUAAUCUACCAUUUAUAACUUAACUAAUUAUGACACCCAAGUCAGUUCUGGGCAAGCAAGAAGUAUCUCUGGGCAAAGAGUCCUGGCGUAAGGUUCCUGGGCACAUCUUUGAGUGCCUGUUAAAGUUAAACUUCAUAUCAUUUCCGGGUAGGAUUCAGAUGAUUAUAAUACUUAGAUGAUAUUUAUAAAACUAAGUAUUUUAGCUCUUGAAGAUAUCUGCUGUCAUUACUGAAACACCACUGGGGAGUGUGUGUGUGUGUUUUAAUCCAGGUCUUUCCAACCAUCUUUUUGUUUUUUUGAGAUGGAGUUUCGCUCUUGUCACCCAGCCUGGAGUGCAAUGGCAUGAUCUCGGCUCACUGCAACUUCCACCUCCCAGAUUCAGGUGAUUCUUCUGCUUCAGCCUCCCAGGUAGCUGGGAUUUCAGGCGUCCACCACCACACCCAGCUAAUUUUUGUAUUUUUAGUAGAGAUGGGGUUUCACUGUGUUGACCAGGCUGGUCUUGAACUCCUUACCUCAAGUAAUACGGCCACCUCCGCAUCCCAAAGUGCUGGGAUUCCAGGCAUGAGCCACUGCGCUCAGCCUUUCCAACCAUCUUAAUUGUUCUGUUGUCAAGAGAAUUAUUGGAUCUGUGAAAUGCAUUGACUUGCAGGGAGCUAGAUUCAUCAGUAGCAUUUAUGCGGGAUUAUUCACUUUUCUAAUAAAUGUUUUUGAGUAUCUGCUUUGUGCCAGGCCCGUGCUGAGGAGGGAUAUGGCUGUGGAUGAAACACAGUACCUGCUUAGCACUUGAAGGUGCAGCAAGCCAGCAAGCACAGCACCUAAACCUCACAGGCGGAGCUUAGUAAAAAAGUGGCAAGGGAUUCGAGAGAAGUCAGCCAGCCUAGGCUUGGGCAAUCAGGGCAGUCAGGUUGCCCAGAGAAAGGAACAUGCAGGCAGCGGGCCAGCCUUUGACCCUCAGGAGGUGGGGGAUGGAGGGAGAACAUUCAAGGGACCAGCAUGUGCAAAGAGCAGGAGAAAAUAGUGGGCGGGAGAGGAGAGCGAGUGGGGGAGUUUGGAGAGAGCAAUAGGAUGGAGUGUAAAGGGGCAGCGGGCAGAGAGAGUUGAGUGGUGGACAGAUUGCUUUGUAGUGACCUUGUAGAUCAUGCAGAGGCAUUUGGGCACCAUCCUGAGGACAGAGGGAAGCCACUGGAGGAGAGUUGCGUGAUCAGAUCAGUGCCUUCGAGUGAUGGCCCCAGCCUGCAGCAGAAAGGAUGCUGGAGACAGGAGUACACCCAAGACUAGAGGCAGGGAGGUGGCAAAACUGAGUGCAGCAUGGGUACGGAGAAGGGGACAGAAGAGAGAGCAGGUGGGAGAAUCCACAGGUCUUGGUGACUAAUCGUGCAUGGACCUAGGGGAAAAGGAAGUAAGGGUGUUACCUAGGUUCCUGGCUUGUGCGCUGGGACGAUGGUGCACUGGUGCCAUUUGUUGAGGGAAGAGGCAGAGAAACAGGUCUGGAGGGGAGGUGAUUACUUCUGUUUGGGGUAUGUUAAGUUUGAGAUGUUCAAAUGAAGAAGUCCUAGGUUGAAAGGUGAAGAAUGGGUCUGAGUACAGAGACCAGAGAUGGAUGUAGAUUGAGAACCAGUGGUGUGCCGGUGACUUCUGAAGCCAUGAGAGCAGGUCUUAGCACUUGAGGACUGCGUAGGGAAAAGCUCUCCAACCGCGUGUGUCCUCUGCUCUCACCGCCAACAGUCAACACAGAAGAAGACUUGUGUGACCGGAUGUAUAGGAGUUUCCCCACACACCAAGCAGCGGCCACCAGCUAGGUGUCUCCGCAUUCUGUUCUGACACUGCCUACCUGGAGAUAGUGUCAGAGCCCACGGGUUGAGGGCUCAGCAGCAAGUCCAGGCUCUGGAACCUCUGACCCACCAGCUUCAAGGUGGGGUUUCCAUGGCUUCCUGUUUGGAUUUGAUUAAUUUGCUGGAGCAACUCACAGAGCUCAGGGAAAACCUUAUGUUUAUGGGUUUAUUAUACAGGACACUGCAAAGGAUACAGAUGAAGAGACACAUAGGGCGAGGUAUGGGAAAGGGGCAUGGAAGCUCCCCGUCCUCUUGGGUUUUUAUGGGAGCUUCAUGACAUCAGCAUUCCUUCCCCCGAGGUCUAGGGGGGACCCUCUCCUGGAGGUCUUAAGACCCACCGUCAGAAAGGCGGAGAGGGAACAGUGGAGUGGAAGGAGGGCAGGAGAAGGUGGGGUCCUAGCGCCCCUGAGGCUCACGCACCUGGCAUUCUAUCAAAAGACUAACCAGGGCCGUGAGGAGCCAGGAACGGGGAGGAAAACCAGUGUCUCUCAUCACACCCCAGGAACGUGGCUUGGGGCACUCUGGCUUUUAUGGGUUGAGUGGAGGAGGAGUCACAGAGCAACUGAGGACCAGCCCAGGAGUGGGAGAAGAAGGUGUGGUGGCUGCUGGCCAUGUAAAAUCCUGUCAGAAACUUCUAGGAGCUUCUUGAAGACAAACUUGAACCUCAUUUGGAAUGUCAGAUGUUGCUUAUUCUUCUCAUUCUUAAGUAACCUUGACAGAGUUAAACACUUCUGUUCCGACUAUGGGAUGUGAAUGCAGUACUUGACAGAGUUAAACACUUCUGUUCCGACUAUGGGAUAUGAAUGCAGUACUUGACAGAGUUAAACCCAGGAACUAUAAACAACUGCAUUCAAGUCACCUGUACAUGAAUUUUCCACGGGGGAGCAGGGCUGCCUCCCAAACCACUUACCAGGGAGGAAAGAUGCCCAGAGGGGACAGUGACUGCCUGCUACCUGAGCGUGAGAGGGCACCGGGCACCGCAGGGGCCCACUCUGACCUUGCUCCCGCGCCUCAUUCCUAGUUACAGUCUGCACUGUAGACAUCCAGCCUCCAGCACCUCCCCCCACCACAUGAGUCCCCAUCCAGCAAGUAAGGUCCACACUUGACUCCCUGCGGUAACUACUCUUCAGCAGUGAAAACAAGCAGCAAGUUUUGCCAGGCAAUAGUUAUUUAUACUGACUUUUCCGAGAUGGAGUCUCACUCUGUCACCCAGGCUGGAGUGCAGUGGAGCGAUGUCGGCUCGCUGCAACCUUGGCCUCUCAGGUUCAAGCGAUUCUCCCGCCUCAGCCUCCCAAGUAGCUGGUACUACCAGCGCACACCGCCACGCACGGCUGAUUUCUUUUUUAUUUUAGUAGACAAGGUUUCACCGUGUCACCCAGGCGGGUCUCGAUCUCCUGAGCUCAGGCAGUCCGCUCGCCUCGCCCUCCCAAAGUGCUAGGAUUACAGACGUGAGUCACCGCACUCAGCCCUGACUUUUCUCAUAUUCACAAAAACUCAUUCCCUCAGCAGUGGGCAAAUAUGAAAAAGACAGCAAUCCAGUGCCCAUGAAAUAACUUUCAGAGGAAAGUUACAGGGGAAAAUUUGCAGCUGGAGUCCAUCCACAAAUUUUGUACUUCAGUUAAGCUAUUAAAUUUAUAUUAUUCACUUUUUGACUUAGUGACUUCCUAACCUGAAGGCAAUGAAAACUCUCAGUGUUUAGAGCCAUAGUUUAUGAGGUUAUCAGCCAUAGAAGAUGCAGUUUUCACAAAGCAUCUAAAUCCAUGCAGCUGUGUAAAUGAGGCCUUGUUCUCAUGGCUCUGUUCCAUUCAGAGAGCUUCCUAUUGGAAUUGUUUUUGAUAAAGGGGAAAGACCAUAGACUGUCUAUCAAAGGACAACAUUAGAUUCCUUUGAAAGGCUUUUCAUUAUUUUCCAUUAAAAAAAUCCUUGCAUUUGUGCAUGCUUUUUGCAUGCUUUUUAUGUUUUUUUAAGUACUUACGCCUAUUAACUUAUUUAUCCUUAUAACCCUUUGACGUAGGUAGUGAAGGAAUUAUUCCUAAUAGCAGAAACCCAUAAAAUGUUAGUAUGGAAAUUAGCUUGAACCCGCUUCUCUAAUCCCUUUCUGCCCUUUUCCCCUUGUUGAUUUCUAGUGCGGUGGAGUAGCUUUCUGUUACAUUCUGCGCAGAUGACUUGCUGGCUUGCUCACUGGCCUCAUCACCAUGAUUUCAGGCUAGAAUUCUUGCUGUGGCCUCCAUGUGGGCCUGUCCUCUGCUCCUCUGCACGGCGGCUGCCCUGGAGCUCUCCCAUGCCCCUACUCCCUCCUGCCCUUUGUUCAUCUCCAGAACAUUCACGUGCCACCUUGGGGAUGGGGAGAGGGAUGCUGUGGUUCCCCCUUUGAGUUCUUCCCCCUGAACUUCACCCUCUAUCUCGGUCCCAUUGACCUCCCAAGCUCUUCUUUCAUGGUUCCCACUCCUUCUCAUUCCAUAGAAAGAUCAGCAGCUGACUUGAGAAGGAACUUUCCUUCUCAGUGAAAAUAACAGUUGCUCUACUUCUGAACUCCAAGGCCUACUUUUUGCUGCAGAUAGGAAGGCUCAGCAGGUUACCCUCAUCUUGUUGAUGCACAUCAGGGUGUGGGGUGUCGUACAGCGAAGCAGGGACAUGGAAAUGGAUUCAUUGGGAACAGAGGUUGAGUGGCUUCUCGGCUGUGCCUUGUCUUGCCUCGCUUCGGAGGAAGCUAGUUGCCUUGACUCCUAGCUGCCACUUAGAUCCACCGCAGCUUUUCAUGCAGGAGCCAUUUGGGCUGAGGGCAGGAUCCUGCAGCCACUGGAGACCUGGCUGCCACACCCACACCUACACCACCAGCAAGCCCCAUCCUCUUCCCCCAGCCCACUCCACUCCAGGGCACUCUCACCUGAUGCCUAGUUCCAGAUUCCGGACUGUCACAGGAAACUACCCUUAUUAGAACUCAUCCACCCUGCCGCUGUGAGUGCUGAGGCUUGGCCGAGUCUCCGUUCCUCCCUUCGAGUUCUCCAUUCCUCAGUUGGUGAACGGGCUGUGUGCACCCCUCAUAGCCAUCCAUACAGCUAACUUGGUUAUUCUCAUGUGUGUCAUUCAAAAGUUCUAAAUUCUAAAGCCAGGCCAGAGCUUUUGUGACCUGGUUCGCUUUAAGGGCAACCUCUUCAAAGAGGUUCUACUUAAAGUUCCAGGUCAUGACAUUUUUCUGCUGGAAUUUGGUUGGGCCCUUGGAGUUUUCUUACAGGAAUUUGUCCCUCAGCAGGCAAAAUAUUGAUUCAUGGUGCAAAGAUCAUAGCUACGUGAUUGCUGGUUAUUAUCAAGCUAAUGAGCGAGUAAAGGAUGCCAGUCCAAACCAGGUUGCAGAGAAGGUGGCCUCCAGAAUCGCCGAGGGCUUCAGCGACACUGCGCUCAUCAUGGUAGACAACACCAAGUUUACGAUGGACUGCGUAGCGCCUACGAUCCACGUGUACGAGCACCAUGAGAACAGAUGGCGGUGCAGAGACCCACACCAUGACUACUGUGAAGACUGGCCAGAGGCACAGAGGAUCUCAGCCUCGCUCCUGGACAGCCGGUCCUACGAGACGCUCGUGGAUUUCGAUAACCACCUGGAUGACAUUCGGAAUGACUGGACAAACCCAGAGAUCAAUAAAGCUGUCCUACACUUGUGCUAGGCAGGCACCGCUGUGACUGGGCUCCGGGCCUUUCCACUACGUUGAAGAAGAAAACCUAUUUUUAAAUGUAAAUAAAAUAUCUUGUAGCCUGUGUGGAAAGCUGACCGUUUUAAGAAGUGGCAUGUGCCUUGAAAGGGGGCAGAAUGUUCAGUCGGUCGUGUUUUUAACACAGAGUCUCUAGAAGAGGUGCAGACAUCCCGUCUGACUGUCCCUGUGGACUCUCUCAGUUGUAUGUUGCUAUAAUCCUCCAAAUCAAAGCUCUUUCUGCUUGUGCAAGAUUGUUCCUAUUAAACAGUUUUAACUAACCUUUUAUAAUCUGGAGAGAAUACUUUUUAAGGCUUUUGAACUAUCUUUUUUUAAAAAAAAAAAAAAAAGCCCACAUCUUAUACUCCAAUGAGUGUGUUUGUGAGUUUUUAUCCUGUUUGAAUUUUGAUGUCGUCCAGGCGUCCUGGGAUCAGGGUAGACACGUGGAGUGCUGGUGCUGAGCUGUUUGAGAAGCUCUGUGUGGGUGUUUCUGUGGUCAGGUAGGCUGGGCUGUGAACAGCACUGCUCCACAUGGUGUCGGCUCACAGAGCCACCGCAACUCUGCCCAGCGGGAGUGACACCACUGAUGCCACAGAAGCCUUUAUCGUUAGGGGCAAAAGCAGACAUCUCUGGUAGCAGGAGCUCAGUGUGGUGCUCUUCAGCCACGCAGAAAGCUCACGUGCCUGCAGGGCCAGGAAAGGGAAAUGAUCGUUUCUUUUGUAUUAGGAAAAACAAGACUUAGACUUCCCGAGUUGUGCAGAGUGACGUCUGUACUUUUUAUACUUAGAACAUUUGGUCAAGUUUUGUAACCAAACCUUAGGGAAUUGAGAGGGAAACUUUAUGGUACGUUUACCUUUUUUCCUUUUUAUAUGAAUUAUUUUGUACAAAGUUCAGAGAGCGGUACCUUUCCUACUGUCUUUUCUUUGACUCCAUGGAGGAAUUUGUAACGAUCGGUGUGACCUGAAAGGGUUUGUGAUACAGCGGUCACUAUUUUCUCUUAACACAUAGGAAAAAAGUUCAGACAUCGCUACAAUAAAUGUGCUUUAUUUGAUCCACCAAA